AAUUUGUUUAUCAGUUCAAAGAGAUUUUUGCUGGAGUCUUUUUUUUUUUUAAUAUAUAAGAGCAUAUUGUCUGAAAACAGACAAUUAGAGCUCCUCCUUUCCACUUUGGGUGCCCUUGAUUUCUUUCUCUUGCCUGAUUGCUCUUGACUAGGACUUUCAGUACUGUGUUGAAUAGGAGUGGUACAAGUGGGCGUCCUUGUCUUGCUACAGAUCUCAGAGAAAAAGCUUAGUGUUUCCCCGUUCAGUAUUAUGUUAGCUGUGGGUUUGUCACAUAUGGCCUUUAUUGUGUUGAGGUAUGUUUCCUUCAGUGCCUAGUUUGUUGAGAGUUUUUAUCAUGAAGCAGCGCUGAAUUUUAUCAAAUGCUUUUUCUGUAUCUAUUGAAAUGAUCCUAUGGCUUUUGUCCUUAAUUCUGUUGAUGUGAUGUAGCGUGUUUAUUGGUUUGUGUUUGUUGAGCCAUCCUUGCAUCCUGGGAGAAAUCCCACUUGAUCGUGGUGUAUAAUAUUUUUGAUUUGCUGUUGGAUUCAGUUUGUUAGUAUUUCGUUGAGGAUUUUUGCAUCUGUGUUCAUCAGGGAUAUUGACCUAUAGUUUUCUCUUUUUAUUGUGUCCUUGUCUUACUUUGGUAUCAGGGUAAUGCUGGCCUUGAAGAAUGAACUUGGCAGAAUUCCAUCCUCUUCAAUAUUUUUGGAAUAGUUUGAGAAGAAUUGAAAUAAAAAUUUGUAGAAUUCAGCUGUGAAGCCACCUAGUCCUGAGGUUUUCUUUGUUGGGAGACUUUUUAUUAUUACUUAGUCAUACAUGUUACUCAUUAUUGGUCUGUUUAGGAUUUCCGUUUCUUCUUGGUUCCGUCUUGGUAGGUUGUACACGUCCAGGAAUCUAUCGAUUUCCUCUAGGUUUUCCACUCUGUUGACAUAUAGUUGUUCAUAAUAGUCUCCAGUGAGCCCUUGUAUUUCUGUGGUAUCAAUUGUAAUUCUCUUUUUCUGUUUCUAAUUUUACUUAUUUGGGAUUUCUUUUUUUUUCUUAGUGUAGCUAAUGGUUUGUCUAUUUUAUUUAUCUUUUCAAAAAACCAACAUUUUUUCCCAUCUUUUGUAUUUUUUAGUUUAAUUUUAUUUAGUUCCUCUUUGAUCUUUGUUAUUUCUUUUCUCCUACCACUUUUGGAUUUGAUUUGUUCUUGCUCUUCUAGCUCAUUGCAGUUCAUUGUUAGGUUGUUUAUUUUAAAUCUUUUUUUUAAUGUAGGAGUUUAUUGCUAUAAACUUUCCUCUUAAUACUGCUUUUGCUCUAUACCGUAGGCUGUGAUAUGUUGUGUUUCUGUUUUCAUUUGUUUCAAUAAAUUUUUAAAUUUCCUUCUUAAUUUCUUCAUUGACCCACUGGCUAUUCAAGGGCAUAUUGUUUAAUUUCUAUGUAUUUAUACAGUUUUGAAAGUUCUUGUUGUUGAUUUAUAGCUUUAUUCUGUUACAGUCUGAGAAUAUCCUAGAUGUGAUUUCAAUUUUAAAAAAAUGUAUUGAGACUUAUUUUGUAGCCUAGCAUGUGAUUGAUUCUAGAGAAUGUUCCAUGUGCUGAGGAGAAGAAUGUGCAUUUUGUAUCUGUUGGAUGAAAUGUUCUGUAAAUGUCUGUUAGGUCCAUUUGGUCUAUACUGUACUUUAAAUUCGAUAUUUUGUUGUUAUUUUCUGUCUAGAUGAUCUCCAGUGCUGAAAGUGGGGUUUUGAAGCCCCUACUAUUGUUGUGUUGGUCUCUCUCUCUCUCUCUCUCUCUCUCUCUCUCUCUCUCUCUAUAUAUAUAUAUAUAUAUUUGAGAUGGAGUUUUGCUUUUGUUGCUUAGGCUGGAGUGCAGUGGUGCAAUCUCGACUCAUUGCAACCUCCACCUCCCAAGUUCAAGUGAUUCUCCUGCCUCAGCCUCCCAAGUAGCUGGGAUUGCAGGCAUGUGCCACCAUGCUCGGUUAAUUUUUUCUAUUUAGUAGACACAGGGCUUUACCAUGUUGGCCAGGCUGGUCUUGAACUCCUGACCUCAGGUGAUCCACCUGCCUCUGCCCCCCAAAGUGCUGGGAUUACAGGUGUGAGGCACUGCACCCCGCCUCUCUAUUUAGAUCUACUAAUAUUUGCUUUAUAUAUCUGGGUGCUUUGUUGUUGGGUGCACAUAUAUUUGUAAUUGUUAUGUCCUCUUGCUGUGUUGAUCUCCUUAUCAUUAUAUAAUUACCUUUUUGUCUCCUUUUUACAGUUUUUAACUUAAAUUGUGAUUAAUCUGAAAUAAAUAUAGCUACUCUUGCUCACUUUUGAUUUCCAUUAAUGUGAAACAUGUUUUUCCAUCCUUCAUGUUUAGUCUAUGUGUGUCUUUACAGCUGAAGUGAGUUUUUUGUAGGCAGCAUAGAGUUGGUUUUUCUUUUUUUAAAUCCACUCAGCCAGUCUAUAUCUUUUAAUUGGGGUGCUUGGGGUUAUUUUGCUACUGAUAUCACAGUCCAGACAUUAAGAUUUUCUCACUUAGUUACUUGUACACAAAUUAAUAUGAAAAGGAAGUAGAGUUUUUCUUUUGUCUCUUUGAAGAUAGUGAUGGAUUAUUAUUUUGAUUUCCAUACAAGUGAGGGACUCACCGUCCCUGUUGGGAUUUUAGAAUUCAUUUCCUGUUAUUAGGAACAGCAAUGAUCUGUAAUGGGUUCCUGGAAUCCUCCAGUGAUGGUCUCAAUAUCUUAAAAGUUUCCUUUCAUGCCUCAUUUUCUGUUUCGCCCCUAGUAGCCACGCACCUGGGGCAGGAGACGGCCUUGCAUUUCCUUGUUUUCUUGAUGACUGGUUAGGUUUAGUGUUUGACACAGUUAGGAUUCUGGAUAAAAUCAGCCCUUCUGGGAAGUGUGUAAGUCAAACAAGGACGUUCUGGUGGCGUUAUACAGGUUUCCCAUGCCCCAUGAGUACAGGAAUAGCUCCCUGGGGAAGGAGUAUGGGCACAUGAUGGCAGGGAGCCAUUCUUGGAUGGCCCCGUCUUCUGCAGGAAUUCUCAUGCAGGGAGAAGCAGCACACGGCGACUGAGCGGGUGGGGAUUCUGCUGAUAGUUUUGAUUGUUAUGAUUUGCUCCUGAAAGGUGAUGUGGGAUGAAGAGCAAUAUUUAGAAUGCUGACAUUCCUUGAAACAAAGAUAUAGAAAAAAUCUUAUAAUUGUAGGGUGCCUUUUAGUUUUCAGCCGCUCUCAUGUGGAUCCUUUUUCGUCCUUCUGAAAUGCUUUCCCAGGAGACAGCAUUGCUCUCUUUGUACAGAUGAGGAGACUGGGUUUCAAAUGGUUAGGAAUUCAUCGCAGGCAUUGGAAUCUUUGGUUUCCUGGAACAUUUUCUAUUCAAGUAUAGACCACGUGGCCUCUAAAGGCUGGCUCACUCUUAACACCAAGAUUGGGGAUCCAGCCUCACCUCUGGGGUGGGCGGCAGGAGCUCCACAGCCAUCCUGGGUGCUCUGGGGUGGGGUGGCUGAGCUGUGGCAGCCCCUCCCAGCUGAGCAGCAAGGCCGGGGAAAGCUCAUUCCAUCCCCCUUGGUUCUAACCAGGUACAGGCUUACACUGCACAUUUCCUUAGCUGGGAACCUUUAGAACUUUACAUUUAAAAUCUAAUCUGUGAUCCAGGGGGUUGAUACAUGGGUAUUCACUGUACAAUUCCUACAUUUUUUGUACAUGUAAUUUUUUUUUAUGUGUGUCAUGGAUGACAAAAGAAAUGCAACCCCUCCGAGUUAGCUUUUCUGUAUAGCACCUUCUAGAAUCAGGAGGCUGGGCAGGGUUUAGUUUCAUCAGAAAUCUUUAUGUUUCUGGUCAAGAGACGGCACUAUUAAAUUCUUGGUUGUGUGGUUUCUGGAAAAGAAAUAUUCUAAAUGAGUUCCAGGAAUCACCUCUGUGGCAUUUCUACAGGAAAAGUGACCACUCUUGAAGCUUCGCCAUCACUCACAAGAAUGAUUGUGAUGGUUUCUAAGCGGUCGCCAGCCAAUCUUUAGUUCUUUUAUGCAGAGUGCUUUCAUUCGAAGUGAAGUGCCCUUCUGUUUAAUGGUGACCUCCAGUUAUUACAGGGAUUGCAGCCGCAUUUGAUGGAUGUGAACCUGCUCAUCUCUGGCUCCCCAGCCUCGCCUCUGGGGUGGGCGGCAGGAGCUCCACAGCCAUCCUGGGUGCUCUGGGGCGGGGAGUCCCUAGUGGGAGUGGACAGUGCAUGGCCGGGACGUUCCUGUCCGAUGUUCCACACUGGCGUGUGCGCGUCUCUGGCCUGUUUCCUUCGUCCGUGGGUCUGUGGCGUUUUCUCCAUGCGUGCGUGUGUGGCCUGUUUUCUCCGUGCGUGCCUCUGUGGCGCGUUUCCUCCAUCCGUGCAUCUGUGGUGUUUCUUCCGUCCCUGCGUCGGUGGUGUUUCUUUCGUCCGUGUGUCUGUGGUGUUUCCUCCGUCCAUGCGUCUGUGGCCUGUUUCCUCCGUCCAUGUGUCUAUGACGUUUCCUCCCUCCGUGCGUCUGUGGCCUGUUUACUCCGUCCGUGCGUCUGUGGCGUUUCCUCCGUCUGUGUGUCUGUGGCCUGUUUCCUCCUUCCGUGCGUCUGUGGCUUUUCCUCCGUCCGUGCGUCUAUGGCCUGUUUCCUCCUUCCGUGUGUCUGUGGCCUGUUUCCUCCUUCCGUGUGUCUGUGGCCUGUUUCCUCCUUCCGUGCGUCUGUGGCUUUUCCUCCGUCCGUGUGUCUAUGGCCUGUUUCCUCCUUCCGUGUGUCUGUGGCCUGUUUCCUCCUUCCGUGCGUCUGUGGCGUUUCCUCCGUCCGUGCGUCUGUGGCCUGUUUCCUCCGUCCGUGCGUCUGUGGCGUUUCCUCCGUCCGUGCGUCUGUGACGUUUCCUCCGUCCGUGCGUCUGUGGCGUUUCCUCCGUCCGUGCGUCUGUGGCGUUUCCUCCGUCGGUGCGUCUGUGACGUUUCCUCCGUCCGUGCGUCUGUGACGUUUCCUCCGUCCGUGCGUCUGUGGCGUUUCCUCCGUCGGUGCGUCUGUGACGUUUCCUCCGUCCGUGCGUCUGUGACGUUUCCUCCGUCCGUGCGUCUGUGGCCUGUUUCCUCCGUCCGUGCGUCUGUGGCCUGUUUCCUCCGUCCGUGCGUCUGUGGCGUUUCCUCCGUCCGUGCGCCUGUGGUCUGUUUCCUCCGUCCGUGCGUCUGUGACGUUUCCUCCGUCCGUGCGUCUGUGACGUUUCCUCCGUCCGUGCGUCUGUGGCCUGUUUCCUCCGUCCGUGCGUCUGUGGCGUUUCCUCCGUCCGUGCGUCUGUGGCGUUUCCUCCGUCUGUGGAUCUGUGGUGUUUCCUCUGUCUGUGAGCCUGUGGCCUGUUUUCUCCGUCCACGCUGGAGGCCGUCGCUUCUCUCUAGUCACCACUUACUGAUCGCUGUGUGCUGAGCCUGUGUCAGGCGUGUGGCAUGUGUCCCCUGUGUGGCAGGGGUUUGCGUGACACACAGGGACACACGCUCGGGGAGCCGCAGGGAUGGGGUCAUAGCCACGUAGCGGAGCCCUCGGUCUGAGGGGCUUGGUGCCCACCCAGCUCUUCCUGAAGCGGCCUCGGGGCAGAUCCCAGCUCUGCUUCCUCUCCUGGAGGCACCUCAUGAAGUAAAUUAAGCAAAUCCAAGGUGACAUCACACAAAAAGGAUAUGAAAAGAAGAGGUCAAAGUUAAUUGGAGCCUACCUUCCGCAGCCUCCGAGGGUGGACCAAGCUUUGCCGCAAGAACGCCGGGCUCCUGUCACUCCUUCCUCCGCCUCUCGCUACCACCGCCGACGGUCUUCAGGGUCACGAGAUGAGCGCUAUCGGUCAGACGUCCACACGGAAGCUGUCCAGGCGGCUCUGGCCAAACACAAAGAGCGGAAGAUGGCAGUGCCUAUGCCUUCCAAACGCAGGUCCCUGGUCGUGCAGACCUCGAUGGACGCCUACACCCCUCCAGAUACCUCUUCUGGCUCAGAAGAUGAAGGCUCAGUGCAGGGGGACUCCCAGGGCACCCCCACCUCCAGCCAGGGCAGCAUCAAUAUGGAGCACUGGAUCAGCCAGGCCAUCCACGGCUCCACCACGUCCACCACCUCCUCGUCCUCUACGCAGAGCGGGGGCAGCGGGGCUGCCCACAGGCUGGCGGACGUCAUGGCUCAGACCCACAUAGAAAAUCAUUCUGCACCUCCUGACGUAACCACGUACACCUCAGAGCACUCGAUACAGGUGGAGAGACCGCAGGGUUCCACGGGGUCCCGGACAGCGCCCAAGUACGGCAACGCCGAGCUCAUGGAGACCGGGGAUGGAGUACCAGUAAGUAGCCGGGUGUCAGCAAAAAUCCAGCAGCUUGUCAAUACCCUCAAACGACCGAAACGACCACCUUUACGAGAAUUCUUUGUCGAUGACUUUGAAGAAUUAUUAGAAGUUCAACAACCGGAUCCGAACCAACCAAAGCCGGAGGGGGCCCAGAUGCUGGCCAUGCGCGGAGAGCAGCUGGGCGUGGUCACGAACUGGCCGCCGUCGCUGGAGGCCGCACUGCAGAGGUGGGGCACCAUCUCGCCCAAGGCGCCCUGCCUGACCACCAUGGACACCAACGGGAAGCCCCUCUACAUCCUCACUUACGGCAAGCUGUGGACAAGAAGUAUGAAGGUCGCUUACAGCAUUCUACACAAAUUAGGCACAAAGCAGGAACCCAUGGUCCGGCCUGGAGAUAGGGUGGCACUGGUGUUCCCCAACAAUGAUCCGGCUGCCUUCAUGGCGGCUUUCUACGGCUGCCUGCUGGCCGAGGUGGUCCCCGUGCCCAUCGAGGUGCCGCUCACCAGGAAGGACGCAGGGAGCCAGCAGAUAGGUUUCUUGCUUGGAAGCUGUGGAGUUACUGUAGCCUUGACUAGUGACGCCUGCCAUAAAGGACUUCCAAAAAGCCCAACGGGAGAGAUCCCACAGUUUAAAGGUUGGCCAAAGCUGCUGUGGUUUGUCACAGAGUCUAAACAUCUCUCCAAACCGCCCCGAGACUGGUUCCCACACAUUAAAGAUGCCAAUAACGACACUGCGUAUAUUGAGUACAAGACGUGUAAGGAUGGCAGUGUGCUGGGUGUGACGGUGACGAGGACUGCGCUGCUGACACACUGCCAGGCCCUGACGCAGGCGUGUGGCUACACGGAAGCUGAAACCAUUGUGAAUGUGCUGGAUUUCAAGAAGGACGUCGGGCUCUGGCAUGGCAUCCUGACAAGCGUCAUGAACAUGAUGCAUGUGAUCAGCAUCCCGUACUCGCUGAUGAAGGUGAACCCUCUCUCCUGGAUCCAGAAGGUCUGCCAGUACAAAGCAAAAGUGGCGUGUGUGAAAUCGAGGGAUAUGCAUUGGGCAUUAGUAGCACACAGAGAUCAGAGAGACAUCAACCUCUCCUCUCUGCGAAUGCUGAUAGUGGCGGACGGCGCGAACCCCUGGUCUAUUUCUUCUUGCGAUGCAUUUCUCAAUGUCUUCCAAAGUAAAGGCCUUCGACAGGAGGUCAUCUGUCCUUGUGCCAGCUCGCCAGAGGCCCUCACUGUGGCCAUCCGGAGGCCCACGGAUGACAGUAACCAGCCCCCGGGCCGGGGUGUCCUCUCCAUGCAUGGACUGACCUAUGGGGUCAUUCGUGUGGACUCGGAAGAGAAGCUGUCCGUGCUCACCGUGCAGGAUGUCGGCCUCGUGAUGCCUGGAGCCAUCAUGUGUUCAGUGAAGCCAGACGGGGUUCCUCAGCUGUGCAGAACGGAUGAGAUCGGGGAGCUGUGUGUGUGUGCAGUUGCGACGGGCACGUCCUACUAUGGCCUCUCUGGCAUGACCAAGAACACCUUUGAGGUGUUUCCCAUGACAAGCUCCGGGGCUCCGAUCAGUGAAUACCCAUUCAUAAGGACAGGCUUGCUGGGGUUCGUGGGUCCCGGAGGCCUCGUCUUCGUGGUGGGCAAGAUGGAUGGCCUCAUGGUGGUCAGCGGGCGCAGGCACAACGCCGACGACAUCGUGGCCACUGCGCUGGCCGUAGAACCCAUGAAGUUUGUCUACCGGGGAAGGAUAGCCGUGUUCUCGGUGACCGUGCUGCACGACGAGAGGAUCGUGAUCGUGGCUGAGCAGAGGCCUGACUCCACGGAAGAGGACAGUUUCCAGUGGAUGAGCCGUGUGCUGCAGGCGAUUGACAGUAUACAUCAAGUUGGAGUUUAUUGCCUGGCCUUGGUGCCAGCAAACACCCUCCCCAAAACCCCGCUUGGUGGGAUCCAUUUAUCAGAAACAAAACAGCUUUUUCUGGAGGGCUCUCUGCACCCCUGCAAUGUCCUAAUGUGCCCCCACACCUGCGUCACAAACUUGCCUAAGCCUCGACAGAAGCAGCCAGAAAUCGGCCCUGCCUCUGUGAUGGUGGGGAACCUGGUCUCUGGGAAGAGAAUCGCCCAGGCCAGUGGCAGAGACCUGGGUCAGAUCGAAGAUAACGACCAGGCACGCAAGUUCCUGUUCCUCUCAGAGGUCUUGCAGUGGAGAGCACAGACCACCCCGGACCACAUCCUCUACACGCUGCUCAACUGUCGGGGUGCGAUAGCGAACUCGCUGACCUGCGUGCAGCUGCACAAGAGAGCUGAGAAGAUCGCCGUGAUGCUGAUGGAGAGGGGCCACCUUCAGGACGGCGACCACGUGGCCUUGGUCUACCCCCCAGGAAUAGACCUGAUAGCAGCGUUUUAUGGUUGCCUGUACGCAGGCUGUGUGCCAAUAACCGUCCGUCCCCCGCACCCACAGAACAUCGCGACGACGUUGCCUACCGUCAAGAUGAUUGUGGAGGUGAGUCGCUCUGCCUGUCUGAUGACGACACAGCUGAUCUGUAAGUUGCUGCGGUCCAGGGAGGCGGCGGCGGCUGUGGACGUCAGGACGUGGCCCCUCAUCCUGGACACAGAUGAUUUGCCAAAGAAGCGGCCUGCCCAGAUCUGCAAACCUUGCAACCCAGACACUCUUGCAUAUCUCGACUUCAGCGUGUCCACAACUGGGAUGCUAGCUGGCGUAAAGAUGUCUCACGCAGCCACCAGUGCCUUCUGCCGUUCCAUUAAGCUGCAGUGUGAACUUUACCCCUCUAGAGAAGUGGCCAUCUGCCUGGACCCUUACUGUGGACUGGGAUUUGUCCUCUGGUGCCUCUGCAGUGUGUAUUCUGGGCACCAGUCCAUCCUGAUCCCGCCCUCUGAGCUGGAAACCAACCCCGCCUUGUGGCUUCUUGCCGUGAGUCAGUACAAAGUCCGAGACACGUUUUGCUCCUACUCCGUGAUGGAGCUGUGCACCAAGGGGCUGGGCUCGCAAACAGAGUCCCUCAAGGCGCGAGGGCUGGACUUGUCCCGAGUGAGGACCUGCGUGGUUGUGGCGGAAGAGAGGCCUCGGAUCGCACUCACACAGUCGUUCUCAAAGCUGUUUAAGGACCUGGGCCUUCACCCGCGGGCCGUCAGCACCUCGUUCGGUUGCAGGGUGAACCUGGCGAUUUGCUUGCAGCCUCACAGGCUGUGGACCCUGGCCGAGCAGGGAACCUCAGGACCUGACCCAACCACUGUCUACGUGGACAUGAGAGCCCUGAGACACGACAGAGUCCGCUUAGUGGAAAGAGGAUCCCCUCAUAGUCUGCCCCUGAUGGAAUCGGGAAAGAUACUUCCAGGGGUUCGGAUUAUAAUUGCCAACCCAGAAACAAAAGGACCGCUGGGGGACUCACACCUUGGAGAGAUUUGGGUUCACAGUGCCCACAAUGCCAGCGGUUAUUUCACUAUUUACGGAGACGAAUCCCUCCAGUCAGAUCACUUCAACUCAAGACUAAGUUUUGGAGACACCCAGACCAUCUGGGCACGCACAGGCUACUUGGGGUUCCUGCGGAGAACUGAGCUCACAGAUGCAAAUGGAGAGCGCCAUGAUGCCCUCUACGUGGUAGGGGCACUGGACGAAGCCAUGGAGCUGCGGGGCAUGCGGUACCACCCAAUCGACAUUGAGACCUCGGUCAUCAGAGCCCAUAAAAGCGUUACGGAAUGUGCUGUGUUUACCUGGACAAAUUUGUUGGUGGUUGUGGUUGAGCUGGAUGGGUCGGAACAAGAAGCCUUGGACCUGGUUCCCUUGGUGACCAACGUGGUCCUGGAGGAGCACUACCUGAUCGUCGGAGUGGUGGUCGUGGUGGACAUCGGCGUCAUCCCCAUCAACUCCCGUGGGGAGAAGCAGCGCAUGCACCUGCGAGACGGGUUUUUGGCAGACCAGCUAGACCCCAUCUAUGUGGCCUACAACAUGUAGUCUCGUCUCUUGGCUUCCAUGGACUUUUCUAGAGAUGUAGACAUUGUUCUCCGUGUCCACUGAAGCGUGCAGACACAGGGCAACACUCACCAGAAUACAGCCAUUUGUGGUGAGAGUGGAGGAGGAAGAGGAGGAGGAAGAGGACUUCUCACAGCAGCCACGAUUGGCAUGGGGGUGAAAUGUGAAUUUACCACUGAAUUUCGCUCAGAAGGACUUUGGAUUACUGCCUUCAGUUUGUUGGAAAAGCCCAUUUCAAAACUUUCUUUUCUUUUCUUUCUUUUUUAAUUAUUGGAUAAUAAGUGCUUUCUUCGUAAAUGUGGUAUUUUGUUAAGCCGAAAUAGCAAUUAAAAAAAUAUCCUGCCCUCCAGAUGGGUUCUUUUAAACAAUUUAUGUAGUGUGACAAAGAAUUGUUUUCUCUGUUUUAAUGUGUCAUGAAAUCUUAAUGACAUGGAUCUGUUACUAAUUUAAGCCAUUGCUAGAUCUCAUCCUUUUAGGAAAGUUUGAGGUACGAGAAAACCUUCCAAAUAGCACCUUCCAAUUAGAUAAUAGCAGCUUUCUUUGUCAGAAAUGUGCUGAAGAAACAAAGGCUGGUAUACGGCCUUCGAAGUUAGUAUAGAAUGAGAAGAAAUUAUAAAUAAGGUGUAUUUCGGCAAUUAUCUUGCAAAUAUCUUUGUACUAAACUAAAAAGAUAAAAUAAGUUAACUUCCUCAAUAUGUAAUUAUGUACAAAACGUUUAAUUUAUUUUGAUCUCUUUAGAACUAUAAAAGAGAAAAACAUUCAAGAAUAUUAAAGUCUUGUAAUGUUUGCUAAUAUAAAAAAGUGUUGUAUUAUCUUGCGUGGAUAGUAUCACAACAAAUAUAUAUAUAUGAAAUAUAAAUUCACUAAUGAACAAAGGAGAUUUUAAAGUUUAAGAUGCAGAACUUGUCACUUGCAUGGUGUGCCCCCCGUACUCACAUACACUCUGCUGUUGCCAGCAGUCGCAGACCGCAGGAGCCCUGUCUAAAAGUUUCUUCUAGAACCAGAGACCAGCAAGUGAAAUUAUUGCCAUCUCAAGGAUGGCAAAAGAAUUCAAAGCUCAAUGUGCACUAUUUUUUUCUUUGCUGUGGGACAACAGUGAAUGUGUUUAUGCCAGCGUGUGCUGAUGAUACUGAGGGGCUUUAGGUUGGCAAAUAGCACUGUUUUCUUAGCUGCAAGAAUUCAUUGCACAAUGUUUUUCAUCAUUUUUGUUAAUGUCAUCUUUUUUUGGUCCUUGCUACGAAAAGGAAUGCGAUUCUGUGGUCAUUCGCACUGGGUUGCAUUGAUUCCCCCUCUGAUGGCCAAUGUGGAGUGGACAAAGUGUCCGGAACUCACAUCGGUGAUCGUCCCCUCGUCUUAAGACCCAGCCCGCUCUGUGUGAGCCUCUGGGGCUCCCUCGCUCAGUGAGCACAGUUCCCCGGGGGUUCAUGCCAGAGCUCCGGCUGAAGCAAGAAGUCCUCCAGCUGCGUCGUUUGCCGCCUGUGGACGAGUGCGCCCCAGUUUCUGCCCUGGCAGCUCCUGGCCACACCUUCUCAGAGCUCACCUGUGCACUUCUAAAUUGAAUUGGCCCACGGUGUCCAACCAAGAAGGAGCAUCUGCACUCCGAGAAAGAUGUGUUCUGUAACUGCCCCAGUGUGACCCCGCAGUGGCUCUCGGUGCUAGAUAUGCAUGACUAAGAUUGAUGCUGGGCAAAAUGUAGAUGAUCUUUCAUUAUGUUGUGGGCAGCGUCUUUCUCUGCCUUUGCUAUAUGCAGUCAGCAGUAAGCCUUUUGCUAAAAGAGUUUUGUUUGACUUCUGAGAUCCAAGGCUGAUUGUUGUUAAAAAAAAAAAAAAAAAAAAAGUGGCACAUUUAAAAAAAUGUGUCUGCAUAUGUGGUGCAUCCUUCCAUCUCCACAAACCAUUUGAUUCUUGAAAUAUUGUUUGACCUCAUUGCUGUGUGUGAAUAUUUCUCCACAUGCUUCAGAUGCACAUUCCUAGUCUCUGCUUCCUAAGGGGGGAACCACCACACAUUGGGGGGAAAAAAGACAUUUUCCUACACCCACCCACCUUGUUGAAAGGGAGGUAGGUUUGGGGCUUCAGGCCAGGCACUGACUAUGAAACAUUAGCUGCAGUGUGCAGGACAGCUUUGAGGUCCAGCUGAAGUCAGGAAGCAAAACAAAUGUAGAUGUCACUUCAAACAUAAUUUCAACUGUCACCAGAUCAACUCUACAUUCAAGGAGUGUGGACGCUGCAGUGCAGUUGUGAGGGCAGUUAGCAGCCGCCUCUUCUGCAUCCUGUCAACUCUGAUUAGUUAGAGUUUAGGCUCAAAAGAGUUGGUGGACUGAGAUUGAAAUUUGGUUGUGCAAGAGAAAGGAAAGGAGACACUUAGUACCACCAGUUUCAGCAAUAAAGAAGGGUCAUUCUGUAUUCAAAAUUGUACUGUAGAUAAAUCAUUCAUGAGAUUGUAAAAAAUGUUUGUCUUGUGACCUUGUGCUUUUGAAGUCAGACAAAACCGUGUAAUCAACUUGCACAAAAAGAGGGUACACAGUGAACAUAUAAACACAGACCUAAUCAAACAGGAGCAGAUUCCUCAUGGUGCUUGUUUAUUAUAUAUAUUUAAUCCUGCUUGACACUUUACCCAAGGGAGAUGGUCCCUUUUAUCAGUUGAAUGUUAGCAGCGUUAUUUCAGAGUGUGGUGACUGGUUAGAGAAACUCAUGUACUCAACCAGCCACAGUUUCAAACAAAAUUUUUAUGUGCAAAGGACAGCAACCUUCUUGUAUGUUAAACCACCAGUACGCUUUGUACAUCUGUGAUAACGCCUGUUUUAUAUUCAAAUGAACAAAUAAAAGCUUUUAUUUUUGUUGCUCUGAAAAUAGCAGUUUCUUAAUUGGUCCCCUGGAAAGAUGUCUGGGACAGCUUUAAUCCCGGGAAGGAAGUGACUCCUACAGGGAAAUGUAUCUGACUCUGUUUACAUAAUUUGUUGCAUUACUUAGUACAGAUAAUCAUACUUUGAAAAAUGUUUAAAUUUUGAUGUGGGCAUUUAUUGCUAAAAAUAAUUCCUAUGGCAACAAAUGUUUUGUGAAAUGUUUUUUUUAAUUCUUUUAAAUAUAUCUAAAUAUAUUUGUUCACA